CUCUGAAGUCAGAAACCUCAUCUCCCACUACAGACCUGCCAGGGCCCAGGAGAGCUCGACCCACCCAGGCACACCAUAGCCCCAGAGAUGGCUGGGGACACAGAAGUGUGGAAGCAAAUGUUUCAGGAGUUAAUGCGGGAGGUGAAGCCAUGGCACAGGUGGACCCUGAGACCAGACAAGGGCCUUCUUCCCAACGUCCUGAAGCCAGGCUGGAUGCAAUACCAGCAGUGGACCUUCGCCAGGUUCCAGUGCUCCUCCUGCUCUCGUAACUGGGCCUCUGCCCAAGUUCUGGUCCUUUUCCACAUGAACUGGAGUGAGGAGAAGUCCAGGGGCCAGGUGAAGAUGAGGGUGUUUACCCAGAGAUGUAAGAAGUGCCCCCAACCUCUGUUUGAGGACCCUGAGUUCACACAAGAGAACAUCUCAAGGAUCCUGAAAAACCUGGUGUUCCGAAUUCUGAAGAAAUGCUAUAGAGGAAGAUUUCAGUUGAUAGAGGAGGUUCCUAUGAUCAAGGACAUCUCUCUUGAAGGGCCACACAAUAGUGACAACUGUGAGGCAUGUCUGCAGGGCUUCUGUGCUGGGCCCAUACAGGUUACAAGCCUCCCCCCAUCUCAGACCCCAAGAGUACACUCCAUUUACAAGGUGGAGGAGGUAGUUAAGCCCUGGGCCUCAGGAGAGAAUGUCUAUUCCUACGCAUGCCAAAACCACAUCUGUAGGAACUUAAGCAUUUUCUGCUGUUGUGUCAUUCUCAUUGUUAUCGUGGUGAUUGUUGUAAAAACUGCUAUAUGAGCCUUGGAAACAUGAAGCUAAGUCAGAAAAAAAAUCAGAUACAAAAAGUCA